GUGCCGCGCUACGCCCGCCGGGAGCCGGGCAGAGCGGCCAAGAUGUCGCAGCCCAAGAAAAGAAAGCUUGAGUCGGGGGGCGGCGGCGAAGGAGGGGAGGGAACUGAAGAGGAAGAUGGCGCGGAGCGGGAGGCGGCCCUGGAGCGACCCCGGAGGACUAAGCGGGAACGGGACCAGCUGUACUACGAGUGCUACUCGGACGUUUCGGUCCACGAGGAGAUGAUCGCGGACCGCGUCCGCACCGAUGCCUACCGCCUGGGUAUCCUUCGGAACUGGGCAGCACUGCGAGGCAAGACGGUACUGGACGUGGGCGCGGGCACCGGCAUUCUGAGCAUCUUCUGUGCCCAGGCCGGGGCCCGGCGCGUGUACGCGGUAGAGGCCAGCGCCAUCUGGCAACAGGCCCGGGAGGUGGUGCGGUUCAACGGGCUGGAGGACCGGGUGCACGUCCUGCCGGGACCAGUGGAGACUGUAGAGUUGCCGGAACAGGUGGAUGCCAUCGUGAGCGAGUGGAUGGGCUACGGACUCCUGCACGAGUCCAUGCUGAGCUCCGUCCUCCACGCGCGAACCAAGUGGCUGAAGGAGGGCGGUCUUCUCCUGCCGGCCUCCGCCGAGCUCUUCAUAGCCCCCAUCAGCGACCAGAUGCUGGAAUGGCGCCUGGGCUUCUGGAGCCAGGUGAAGCAGCACUAUGGUGUGGACAUGAGCUGCCUGGAGGGCUUCGCCACGCGCUGUCUCAUGGGCCACUCGGAGAUCGUUGUGCAGGGAUUGUCCGGCGAGGACGUGCUGGCCCGGCCGCAGCGCUUUGCUCAGCUAGAGCUCUCCCGCGCCGGCUUGGAGCAGGAGCUGGAGGCCGGAGUGGGCGGGCGCUUCCGCUGCAGCUGCUAUGGCUCGGCGCCCAUGCAUGGCUUUGCCAUCUGGUUCCAGGUGACCUUCCCUGGAGGGGAGUCGGAGAAACCCCUGGUGCUGUCCACCUCGCCUUUUCACCCGGCCACUCACUGGAAACAGGCGCUCCUCUACCUGAACGAGCCGGUGCAAGUGGAGCAAGACACGGACGUUUCAGGAGAGAUCACGCUGCUGCCCUCCCGGGACAACCCCCGUCGCCUGCGCGUGCUGCUGCGCUACAAAGUGGGAGACCAGGAGGAGAAGACCAAAGACUUUGCCAUGGAGGACUGAGCGUUGCCUUUUCUCCCAGCUACCUCCCAAAGCAGCCUGACCUGCGUGGGAGAGGCGUAGCGAGGUCGGAGGGGAAAGGGAGAUCCCACGUGCAAGUAGGGGGAAUAUCUCCCCCUUUUCCCUCAUAGCCUCUAGGGAGGGAGAGUGACUUCAUUCUCCAUUUGAAGAGAUUCUUCUGGUGAUGUUUACUUAAAAAGUGAUCCCCCUCAACAACGGAUACAGCGUGCUUAUUAUUGGGCAUUUAGCCUCAAAAGCAUGUAGUACCAAGCACUUGUAUUUCCGUAUAUUUUGUUUCGCGGGGGAGUGAGGGGGAAGAACACGGAUGAAAAUGUCAGUUUUUGAAGGGUCCAUGCACAUCCCUGACACCUCACACCUUAUCUAAGUCUGAAGCUGGGGAGAAAGGGGUUCAUUUAGACUUCAUACAUUUCCAGUACGACUUUAGUAUCUCUCCAGAGCCAUAUUUUCUCAGUCCGAAUUAAUUCCCCCUCCCUAGGUGCCUGUAGGCUAUGGUACUUCUUCCUCAUUGUUUUCUAGGUAAACUUCACUACUGGUAAUUAAGGGGAAGGAUAUGAGGAAGCAGUUUAAAUAGCCCUGUUCUCAUUACUCUGACCACAUACAUCAUAGGGUGCUAAAGUUGAUGAACACAUUAAUCCGUUAAGUAAAAUGGACUUUGUAAUUGUACAGCAUACCUAAGAAACUCAGAAGGUGCAUUUAAGAGAGAGACCUGAAAGAAAUAGUAUGGAUUUUUAAAAAUUCUUGUCUCUACUAUUAUAACCAAAAAAUAUUUCUUGUAUGUCCCAUAAAAAUAUUUGUGUAAUUCUUAUGAAACAGGCUGGUAGAGGAGGUUUCUGAGCCUAGCCCAAGGGCUUAUUCAUCACCAUGGGUAAAUUAUUUAAACUCACUUAAUUAAGGAAAAUAUUUUCCCAGCUAGAAAAGUAUACUCAUUCUCAUUUAAACUCUCUCAUUUGGAGGGAUCAUGUGAGUUGGCCUACUUACAAGUAGUGAAAGUUCCCUUUUCAGUUUUGUUUUGUUUUGUUUUGUUUUUCUCUUUCACUCAGCCAAAUGUGAAAGUUGUGAAUUUAGGAAAAUCACUUGUAAUGAAGUGUGAAUCUUGUUAUCAAAUUUAUUUCUCUGAUGUUUCCUUCCUUAUCCUUGUAGCCAAUAAAACAUUGACAUUCUCACGUUUUAUAGAUGAGGUAAAAAGUCUUGUGUGCUGUGAGUUAUAAUGCUUUUGCCUUUUUAAUAUUAUUAGUUCUUAAGUGUUACAGCCCCUUCAGAAUAUAACUUCAGGACAAUUCAAACUAUGCUUAAUGUAUGAUUUUCGAGCUUCUGUAUGCUAAGAAAAUAGGUGUGAAAAACUGGUGUUCUGAAAUAGCCUAACAUUUAUUGUAAUUCUGAAUUUUCUGCCCUUUUAUUCAUUGCAUAUUAAAGUAUUAGAGUAUAAAAACUAA